GCAGUCGCCCGGGCGACGGCGGGGUCCGCGCGGCCAGGUAAGGUGUGCGCCCAGCAGGUGAGGCGCGGGUGGCGUCGGCAGCUUCAGGGCUCUCCCCGUGGAGGGGGCGCUGUCCCGAGGAGCGGAUAGCCGAGGCCCGGGACGGGGGCGGGGCAGCGCCCAAAGUCGGGGAAACUGAGGCCCGGCGUGGCCCCCGUCCGGCCGAGCCUGGGCGCGCGGGGAUUCUGGCCCUGGGAGCCCCUCGGCUGGGAGCGGGCUGCGGGCUCCGAGGAGGCUCCGGCGGGGCGGCCCCGGCUGCAGGGCGCCCGCGUGCGUCUCGGGGACUGCGCCGGCGAUUCCGCGGUGGCCGAGCCUCGGAGGGGGUUUCCCCAGUUCACGCAGCGAGCAGGAGGCGGAACUGGGCCUGGGCCGGGUCUGUCUCCCAAGCCAGUGCCUAAACGCCCAUCGUCCUGGCGCAUCCUGGGGUUCCCUGGGCCCAGCCGAGUCUGGGUGGCGUCCCCGCAGCUGGGGCUGGAGGGACCGCCUGCUGCGCUCCGUCUUGGUGGGCAGCCCUCAUGACCAGCCCUUGGGAGAGGGGUGCGGGGAGAGGGACAGCCCCUGAUGUCAGUGGCUCAGCACGUGUGACUUUGACCUCCUUCCUGCUGAUCAUUGCUCACCUGAGCGACACGGGGAGGGGGAGGCAGCAGCCUCGUGUGAGGCUUCCAGAGGAAAGCGUCUCCGCCGGCCCGGAGGCGCUGAACCAGCCUGCGGUCGCUGCCAGCUCUGCCUCUGGCCGGCUGUUAACUGAGUUUACAGGUUCACAAGCAUUUCGGGCAUAAACAAGGGGCUUUGUGAAGGAGUGAGGGGACCUGGGCUGCUGAUGCGGCUAACGGUGCUCGCGGGUGGAUGCUUUGGUUUUGUUCCAGUUGGGCAGGGCCCCAGUCAGCCUCCAGCAGGGAGAGCCACGCCAAGGACGGGGGAGGGCGUUUCUCUUUGUUGUUGGGUGUUUUGGGCUCCCGGGUCUGUGCUAGUGAUUCCUUUAGAUUUUCUCUGCUAAUGUUUCAUUCUCCCACUCUCUCUCUAGCGUCCUUCUCCCUUCAGACUUCCUGGACCACAGUUCCUAAGAAAAAAGCUUGACAAACAUUUGUUAGUGUCAGGCACUGCCACGUUCCAGGCGUUGUUCUGGAUGUACAGAGAACAGCCAGCCUUCCCUUUGGGAGCUUCCUUCCCAACCAUGCUGCGGGAGUCAUGGAUGUAGAUGCUGAAAGAGAGAAGAUAACACAGGAGAUCAAGGAGCUGGAAAGGAUUUUGGAUCCCGGCUCCUCGGGCUCCCACGUGGAGAUCUCAGAAUCAAGUCUCGAGUCAGAUUCUGAAGCAGAUUCACUGCCUUCUGAGGACUUGGAUCCUGCCGAUCCCCCGAUCUCGGAAGAAGAAAGGUGGGGCGAAGCCAGCAAUGACGAGGACGAUCCCAAGGAUAAAACCCUCCCUGAAGACCCAGAAACCUGCCUGCAGCUGAACAUGGUCUACCAGGAGGUCAUCCAGGAGAAGCUGGCUGAGGCCAACCUGCUGCUGGCCCAGAACCGGGAGCAGCAGGAGGAACUCAUGAGGGAUCUGGCUGGGUCCAAAGGCACCAAGGUGAAAGAUGGCAAAAGCCUGCCCCCAAGCACAUACAUGGGGCACUUCAUGAAGCCGUAUUUCAAGGACAAGGUCACGGGCGUGGGGCCACCUGCCAACGAGGACACACGAGAGAAGGCUGCCCAGGGGAUCAAGGCUUUCGAGGAGCUCCUUGUGACCAAAUGGAAAAACUGGGAAAAGGCCUUGCUCCGAAAGUCAGUGGUGAGUGACCGCCUGCAGCGAUUGCUUCAGCCCAAGUUACUGAAGCUCGAGUACUUGCACCAGAAGCAGAGCAAAGUCUCCAGUGAGCUGGAGAGGCAAGCCCUGGAGAAGCAGGGCAGGGAAGCCGAGAAGGAGAUCCAGGACAUCAACCAGCUUCCAGAAGAGGCCUUGCUGGGAAACAGGCUGGACAGCCACGACUGGGAGAAGAUUUCCAAUAUUAACUUUGAAGGCAGCCGCAGUGCAGAGGAGAUCCGGAAGUUCUGGCAGAACUCGGAGCACCCCAGCAUCAACAAGCAGGAGUGGAGCAGGGAGGAGGAGGAGCGGCUGCAGGCGAUCGCGGCUGCACACGGCCACCUGGAGUGGCAGAAGAUUGCAGAGGAGCUGGGGACCAGCCGCAGCGCCUUCCAGUGCCUGCAGAAAUUCCAGCAGCACAACAAAGCUCUGAAACGCAAGGAGUGGACAGAGGAGGAGGACCGCAUGCUCACGCAGCUGGUGCAGGAGAUGCGCGUCGGCAGCCACAUCCCCUACCGCAGAAUUGUCUACUAUAUGGAAGGGAGAGACUCCAUGCAGCUGAUCUACCGAUGGACCAAGAGCUUGGAUCCUGGUCUGAAGAAGGGUUACUGGGCCCCGGAGGAAGAUGCUAAGUUGCUUCAAGCUGUUGCCAAAUACGGGGAGCAGGAUUGGUUUAAAAUCCGGGAAGAGGUGCCAGGUAGGAGCGAUGCCCAGUGCCGAGAUCGGUAUCUCAGGAGAUUACAUUUCAGCUUGAAAAAGGGUCGGUGGAAUUUAAAAGAAGAGGAACAGUUAAUUGAAUUAAUAGAAAAAUAUGGUGUCGGUCACUGGGCAAAAAUAGCUUCUGAGCUGCCCCAUCGGUCUGGCUCCCAGUGUCUGAGCAAGUGGAAGAUCAUGAUGGGGAAGAAGCAGGGUCUCCGGAGGCGGCGGCGGAGGGCCCGUCACAGCGUCCGGUGGAGCUCUACCAGCAGCAGCGGCAGCAGCAGUGGCAGCAGUGGAGGGAGCAGCAGCAGCAGCAGCAGCAGCAGCGAGGAGGACGAGCCAGAGCAGGCGCAGGCCGGGGAGGGUGACAGAGCGCUGCUGUCCCCACAGUACAUGGUCCCGGACAUGGACCUGUGGGUUCCUGCCAGGCAGAGCACCAGCCAGCCAUGGAGAGGAGGGGCAGGGGCCUGGCUGGGAGGCCCCGCUGCCUCCCUCAGCCCUCCCAAGGGGUCCAGUGCCAGCCAGGGCGGCAGCAAGGAAGCUUCCACCACAGCCGCGGCUCCUGGAGAGGAGACGAGUCCGGUGCAGGUCCCUGCCAGGGCCCACGGCCCUGUCCCGAGGUCUGCCCAGGCCUCCCACUCAGCAGACACUCGCCCGGCGGGCGCAGAGAAGCAGGCCCUGGAGGGUGGGAGGCGUCUGCUGACAGUGCCUGUGGAGACCGUGCUGAGGGUGCUCAGGGCCAACACGGCUGCUCGGAGCUGCACACAGAAAGAGCAGCUGAGGCAGCCACCCCUGCCCACCUCAUCCCCAGGGGUCAGCUCUGGUGACAGCGUGGCCCGAUCCCAUGUGCAGUGGCUACGGCACAGAGCCACCCAGAGUGGGCAGCGGCGCUGGAGACACGCUCUGCACCGGAGGCUCCUGAACCGCAGGCUGCUGCUGGCUGUGACCCCUUGGGUAGGGGACGUUGUCGUGCCCUGCACACAGGCUUCCCAGAGACCCGCCGUAGUGCAGACUCAAGCGGAUGGCCUCAGGGAGCAGCUGCAGCAGGCCCGCCUGGCCAGCACCCCUGUGUUUACCCUGUUUACCCAGCUGUUCCACAUCGAUACUGCCGGCUGCUUGGAGGUCGUCCGAGAGAGGAAGGCCCUGCCACCCAGGCUGCCCCAGGCUGGUGCUCGGGACCCACCAGUUCAUCUUCUGCAGGCAUCCUCAAGUGCCCAGAGCACCCCAGGCCACCUCUUCCCAAACGUGCCGGCUCAAGAAGCCUCAAAGAGUGCCAGCCACAAAGGGAGCCGAAGACUGGCGUCCAGCCGGGUGGAGCGCACCCUACCCCAGGCGUCCCUGCUGGCUUCAACCGGCCCCCGGCCCAAGCCCAAGACUGUGUCGGAGCUGCUUCAGGAGAAGCGGCUUCAGGAGGCCCGUGCCAGGGAGGCCACCCGGGGCCCGGUGGUGCUCCCGUCCCAGCUGCUGGUCUCCUCGUCUGUGAUCCUCCAGCCCCCUCUACCACACACCCCACACGGCCGCCCAGCCCCGGGUCCCACCGUCUUAAAUGUACCGCUCUCUGGGCCUGGGGCCCCCGCGGCAGCCAAACCUGGCACUUCUGGCUCCUGGCAGGAGGCUGGGACUUCAGCCAAGGACAAGAGACUCUCCACCAUGCAAGCCCUGCCCCUCGCUCCUGUCUUCUCAGAGGCCGAGGGCACAGCCCCUGCUGCUUCCCAAGCCCCUGCCCUGGGCCCCGGCCAGAUCUCUGUGAGCUGCCCCGAGAGUGGUCUCGGACAGUCUCAGGCCCCCGCUGCAUCCCGGAAGCAGGGCCUGCCUGAGGCGCCACCCUUUCUCCCCGCAGCCCCCAGCCCCACCCCACUGCCCGUCCAGCCCCUCAGCCUGACGCACAUAGGAGGGCCACAUGUGGCGACCAGUGUCCCCCUGCCUGUCACCUGGGUGCUCACAGCCCAGGGGCUUCUCCCUGUUCCUGUACCAGCUGUGGUGAGCCUUCCCAGGCCAGCAGGGACCCCUGGCCCCGCAGGGCUGCUGGCCACUCUGCUGCCUCCCCUGACUGAGACUCGGGCGGCCCAGGGCCCCAGGGCCCCAGCGUUGAGCAGCUCUUGGCAGCCCCCAGCCAAUAUGAACAGGGAACCGGAGCCUUCCUGCAGGACAGACACCCCAGCUCCUCCCACACACGCCCUCUCCCAAAGUCCUGCAGAAGCGGAUGGCAGUGUGGCCUUUGUCCCUGGAGAGGCCCAGGUGGCCAGGGAGAUACCUGAGCCCAGGACGUCCUCCCACGCUGACCCUCCUGAAGCAGAACCCCCUUGGUCCGGGAGGCUGCCAGCCUUCGGUGGUGUCAUCCCAGCAACUGAGCCAAGGGGGACGCCGGGGUCCCCCUCAGGGACACAGGAGCCCAGGGGGCCUCUGGGCCUGGAGAAGCUGCCCCUGCGCCAGCCUGGGCCUGAGAAGGGGGCCCUGGACCUGGAGAAGCCGCCCCUACCCCAGCCUGGGCCUGAGAAGGGGGCCCUGGACCUGGGCCUGCUGUCCCAGGAGGGCGAGGCGGCCACACAGCAGUGGCUGGGGGGCCAGCGGGGGGUGCGUGUGCCUCUUCUGGGCAGCAGACUGCCCUAUCAGCCCCCAGCCCUGUGCAGCCUGCGAGCUCUGUCCGGUCUCCUACUCCACAAGAAGGCCCUGGAGCACAAGGCCACCUCCCUGGUGGUGGGGGGCGAGGCUGAGCGGCCGGCCGGAGCACUGCAAGCCUCACUGGGGCUGGUGCGGGGGCAGCUCCAGGACAACCCGGCCUACCUCCUGUUGCGGGCGCGGUUCCUGGCAGCCUUCACCCUCCCUGCGCUCCUGGCCACCCUGGCCCCCCAAGGCGUCCGCACCACCCUCUCAGUACCUUCGAGGGUGGGCUCUGAGAGUGAGGAUGAAGACCUCCUGAGUGAGCUGGAACUUGCAGACAGGGACGGGCAGCCGGGCUGCACGACAGCCACAUGCCCCAUUCAGGGAGCCCCAGACUCUGGUAAAUGCUCUGCUUCCUCCUGCCUGGAUACUUCUAAUGACCCUGACGACCUGGACGUGCUCAGAACCCGGCAUGCCAGGCACACCCGGAAGCGGAGGCGGCUGGUGUGAGCAGCAGGACAAGCACUUUCUCAGAAGCCCGUGGCCCUGCUGACGAGAGACAGCCCACCCCCAGCCUGCAAGAGAGGCAGCCAGAGGCCAGGUAUCUGCUGGCCGCUGACUGACCAGGUCCGCAGUGAACAGAGGCGGGCCUGCCGACUGACUGUGUGGCAUGGAGCAUGGCUGUUCCCCAAGUGCACACCUGAACACUUGGAGGAAUAAAGUUCUGUUUUUAAUUGUGGAGCUGGA